GGAGCCUGAGGGACCCGGCGGCUGGUGAGCGCCCGCUGGAGGCUGGAGCUUCCGGGCCCUGGAAAGGGGUCCCCGCGCGCCCCGGGUCGGAGGCAGACCCCUGGGUUUGGGGGACAUGGGCAUUUGGGGCGCCUGAACCCAAGACCUCUGGAUGGUAGGGAUGCCCGGGCGUCCUGGAUACCCUGCGGGACUCGGGGCUCCUGCGGGGAAGAUGGCACGUUUUACUGCCCAAGGAGUGGUCAGGGGGGUGGAGAAGCGCUGCGGAUACCCUCAGGAGGUCUGCGACAGAGGGGGCUAGCUGCGCAGCCCAGGAGUGGUAGUGGCCCCCCUGGAUGACAGGCCUGGCCGUAUCCUCCCCCAGAGCUGCCCCGUUCAGACCAUGGAUCCUGAGGUGACCUUGCUGCUGCAGUGCCCUGGCGGGGGCCUGCCCCAGGAGCAGAUACAGGCCGAGCUGAGCCCCGCCCAUGACCGUCGCCCACUGCCAGGUGGGGACGAGGCCAUCACUGCCAUCUGGGAGACCCGGCUAAAGGCCCAACCCUGGCUCUUCGACGCCCCCAAGUUCCGCCUGCACUCAGCCACCCUGGCGCCUAUUGGCUCUCGGGGGCCACAGCUGCUCCUGCGCCUGGGCCUUACUUCCUACCGAGACUUCCUGGGCACCAACUGGUCCAGCUCAGCUGCCUGGCUGCGACAGCAGGGUGCCACCGACUGGGGUGACACGCAGGCCUAUCUGGCGGACCCACUGGGGGUGGGCGCUGCACUAGCCACAGCCGAUGACUUCCUUGUCUUCCUGCGCCGCUCCCGGCAGGUGGCUGAGGCCCCUGGGCUGGUGGACGUACCUGGUGGGCACCCUGAGCCUCAGCUGGACCUCUGGUUGUCUGUCAGGGAAAGGACACCAGACUCAGGAUCACUAACUCUCUUACACUGUGCCACAUCAGACCCUCAAGGCCAGCAGGCCCUGUGCCCUGGUGGCAGCCCCCAGCACCAGGACCUCGCUGGGCAGCUGGUGGUACAUGAACUCUUUUCCAGUGUCCUUCAGGAGAUCUGUGAUGAGGUGAACCUGCCGCUGCUCACCCUGAGCCAGCCCCUGCUGUUGGGCAUCGCCCGAAAUGAGACCAGUGCUGGCCGAGCCAGUGCCGAGUUCUAUGUCCAGUGCAGCCUGACUUCUGAGCAGGUGAGGAAGCACUACCUGAGUGGGGGACCCGAGGCCCACGAGUCUACAGGAAUCUUCUUUGUGGAGACACAGAACGUGCAGAGAUUGCUCGAGACGGAGAUGUGGGCUGAACUCUGCCCCUCGGCCAAAGGCGCCAUCAUCCUCUACAACCGGGUUCAGGGAAGUCCCACUGGAGCGGCCCUAGGGUCCCCAGCCCUACUCCCGCCGCUCUGAAAAUAAUAAACGACUUUAUUCUUGGA